UGAGGCAUGUCAGUCACUGCCCCACAACUGGAGCCAGCAACUGGUUCAGAGGUGGCCAUGUGGCCCAACUUACAUCCAUGAUCUGGAAAGGGUCUGAAGGAUCUGCGCCCUGUGUUCAAGGACGACGCUGAAACAUUCUUUUCUGCGUGCCUGAUCUGAGGCCUCACAACUCAGGUGAGCAAGACUGUGUCCCUUUCACAUGGAGAAGCCGAGUUCCACGGAGGUUGAGUGAGGAGCCGGCAUCACACAAGGACUCGGAGGGGCUCCUCGAGACUCGCGGGACAGAGACGGCAGCCCCAGGGGAUCAUGGACAUUGAAGCAUAUUUUGAAAGAAUUGGCUAUAAGAACUCUAGGAACAAAUUGGACUUGGAAACAUUAACUGACAUUCUUGAGCACCAGAUCCGGGCUGUUCCCUUUGAGAACCUUAACAUGCAUUGUGGGCAAGCCAUGGAGUUGGGCUUAGAGGCUAUUUUUGAUCACAUUGUAAGAAGAAACCGGGGUGGGUGGUGUCUCCAGGUCAAUCAACUUCUGUACUGGGCUCUGACCACAAUCGGUUUUCAGACCACAAUGUUAGGAGGGUAUUUUUACAUCCCUCCAGUUAACAAAUACAGCACUGGCAUGGUUCACCUUCUCCUGCAGGUGACCAUUGACGGCAGGAAUUACAUUGUCGAUGCUGGGUCUGGAAGCUCCUCCCAGAUGUGGCAGCCUCUAGAAUUAAUUUCUGGGAAGGAUCAGCCUCAGGUGCCUUGCAUUUUCUGCUUGACAGAAGAGAGAGGAAUCUGGUACCUGGACCAAAUCAGGAGAGAGCAGUAUAUUACAAACAAAGAAUUUCUUAAUUCUCAUCUCCUGCCAAAGAAGAAACACCAAAAAAUAUACUUAUUUACGCUUGAACCUCGAACAAUUGAAGAUUUUGAGUCUAUGAAUACAUACCUGCAGACGUCUCCAACAUCUUCAUUUAUAACCACAUCAUUUUGUUCCUUGCAGACCCCAGAAGGGGUUUACUGUUUGGUGGGCUUCAUCCUCACCUAUAGAAAAUUCAAUUAUAAAGACAAUACAGAUCUGGUCGAGUUUAAAACUCUCACUGAGGAAGAGGUUGAAGAAGUGCUGAGAAAUAUAUUUAAGAUUUCCUUGGGGAGAAAUCUCGUGCCCAAACCUGGUGAUGGAUCCCUUACUAUUUAGAAUAAGGAACAAAAUAAACCCUUGUGUAUGUAUCACCCAACUCACUAAUUAUCAACUUAUGUGCUAUCAGAUAUCCUCUCUACCCUCACGUUAUUUUGAAGAAAAUCCUAAACAUCAAAUACUUUCAUCCAUAAAAAUGUCAGCAUUUAUUAAAAAACAAUAACUUUUUAAAGAAACAUAAGGACACAUUUUCAAAUUAAUAAAAAUAAAGGCAUUUUAAGGAUGGCCUGUGAUUAUCUUGGGAAGCAGAGUGAUUCAUGCUAGAAAACAUUUAAUAUUGAUUUAUUGUUGAAUUCAUAGUAAAUUUUUACUGGUAAAUGAAUAAAGAAUAUUGUGGAAAAA